AAGUCGGCGCGGGCUAGGCGACGGGUGGAAGCCGGUACCGAGAGGAACUACAGCGUCGCCGCCUGGGUUGUGUCGCCGCGGUAGGCGCUGCGCUCUGAGCGCAGCGCAGGCCCCGUACCGACCGCCCGCCCGCCCUCUGUCCGCGAUGGAGGUGCCGGCCGCGGGUCGCGUUCCUGCCGAGGGCGCCCCGACGGCGGCUGUGGCCGAGGUGCGCUGCCCGGGGCCCGCGCCGCUGCGCCUGCUGGAGUGGAGGGUGGCGGCGGGCGCGGCCGUGCGCAUCGGCUCGGUGCUGGCCGUGUUCGAGGCCGCCGCCUCCGCGCAGUCCUCCGGGGCCUCUCAGUCCCGUGUAGCCUCCGGGGGCUGCGUGCGCCCCGCGCGGCCGGAACGCAGGCUGAGGUCGGAGCGCGCGGGCGUGGUGCGGGAGCUGUGCGCGCAGCCGGGCCAGGUGGUCGCCCCAGGAGCGGUUCUGGUGAGGUUGGAAGGAUGCAGCCACCCGGUUGUCAUGAAAGGCCUGUGUGCUGAAUGUGGCCAAGACCUCACCCAGUUGCAGAGUAAGAACGGGAAGCAGCAGGUGCCGCUGUCCACGGCGACCGUGUCCAUGGUGCACAGCGUGCCGGAGUUGAUGGUGAGCUCCGAGCAAGCUGAACAGCUGGGAAGAGAAGACCAGCAGCGACUGCACCGAAACCGGAAGCUGGUGCUCAUGGUGGACUUGGACCAGACGUUGAUUCACACAACCGAGCAGCACUGUCAGCAGAUGUCGAAUAAAGGCAUCUUUCACUUCCAGCUGGGCCGGGGUGAGCCCAUGCUGCACACGCGCCUGCGUCCACACUGCAAGGACUUCCUGGAGAAGAUCGCCAAGCUGUACGAGCUGCACGUCUUCACCUUCGGCAGCCGGCUGUACGCACACACCAUCGCAGGCUUUUUAGACCCCGAGAAGAAGCUUUUUUCUCACCGAAUAUUAUCAAGGGAUGAAUGUAUUGACCCAUUUUCUAAAACGGGAAACCUUAGAAAUCUCUUUCCUUGUGGAGACUCAAUGGUUUGCAUUAUUGAUGAUCGAGAAGAUGUCUGGAAGUUUGCCCCCAAUCUGAUAACUGUGAAGAAAUAUGUAUACUUCCAGGGCACGGGUGAUAUGAAUGCGCCCCCUGGGUCCCGAGAAUCUCAGACGAGAAAGAAAGUAAAUCAUUCUCGAGGCACUGAGGUCUCAGAGCCAUCUCCGCCCGUGAGAGACCCUGAGGGGGUAACGCAGGCCCCUGGAGUGGAGCCCAGCAAUGGCCUGGAGAAGCCUGCACGGGAGCUGAACGGCAGCGAGGCCGCCACCCCGCGGGACUCACCCCGCCCCGGGAAGCCAGACGAGAGGGACAUCUGGCCCCCUGCCCAGGCCCCCACCAGCAGCCAAGAGCUGGCAGGCGCUCCUGAGCCCCAGGGAUCCUGUGCGCAGGGUGGCCGGGUGGCACCGGGACAGCGGCCUGCCCAGGGUGCCACGGGCACUGACCUGGACUUUGACUUAUCCAGCGACAGCGAGAGCAGCAGUGAGUCCGAGGGCACGAAGUCCUCCUCCUCCGCCUCUGAUGGCGAAAGCGAGGGGAAAAGAGGCCGGCAGAAGCCGAAGGCUGCCCCAGAGGGAGCCGGGGCGCUGGCACAGGGCAGUUCCCUGGAGCCGGGGCGGCCUGCAGCACCGAGUCUCCCCGGAGAGGCCGAGCCUGGCGCGCAUGCCCCGGACAAGGAGCCUGAGCUGGGUGGGCAGGAGGAGGGCGAGCGGGAUGGCCUCUGCGGCCUGGGCAACGGCUGUGCCGACAGGAAGGAGGCGGAGACCGAGUCACAGAACAGCGAGCUGUCGGGGGUCACUGCGGGUGAGUCCCUGGACCAGAGCAUGGAGGAGGAGGAGGAGGAGGACACGGAUGAGGAUGACCACCUCAUCUACCUGGAGGAGAUCCUGGUCCGUGUACACACUGACUACUAUGCCAAGUAUGACCGCUACCUCAACAAGGAGAUCGAGGAGGCGCCGGACAUCCGCAAGAUCGUGCCGGAGCUCAAGAGCAAGGUGCUGGCAGACGUGGCCAUAAUUUUCAGUGGGCUACACCCGACAAACUUCCCGAUAGAGAAGACGCGGGAGCAUUACCACGCCACGGCGCUGGGAGCGAAGAUCCUCACUCGGCUGGUGCUGAGCCCCGACGCCCCUGACAGGGCCACGCACCUGAUCGCCGCGCGAGCUGGCACAGAGAAGGUGCUGCAGGCACAGGAGUGCGGACACCUGCACGUGGUCAACCCUGACUGGCUGUGGAGCUGCCUGGAGCGCUGGGACAAGGUGGAGGAGCAGCUCUUCCCGCUCAGGGACGAUCACACCAAGGCACAGAGGGAGAACAGCCCUGCGGCCUUUCCCGACCGGGAGGGUGUGCCCCCCACCGCCUUGUUCCACCCGAUGCCGGUUCUUCCCAAGGCCCAGCCUGGCCCCGAGGUUCGGAUCUACGACUCCAACACGGGGAAGCUCAUCAGGACGGGCGCCCGGGGGCCCCCAGCACCCUCCAGCUCCCUACCCAUCCGCCAGGAGCCCUCUUCCUUCAGGUACGUGGCGGCCCAGCCACUGUCCCAGC